GAGACAGGAUCUCACUGUGUCAUUCAGGCUGGAGUACAGUGGUGUGAUCUCGGCUCACUGCAACCUCUGCCUCCUGGGCUCAAGCUAUCUUCCCACUUCAGCCUGCUGAGUAGCUGGGACUACAGGCGUGUGCCAUCACGCCCAGCUAGUUUUUUUUUUUGUUUUGUUUUGUUUUUGGUAUUAGAGAUGGGGUUUUGCCAUGUUGCCCAGGCUGGUCUCGACCUCCUGGGCUCAAGAAGUCCGGCCGCCUCAACCUCCGACAGUGCUGAGAUUACAGGAGUGAGCCACUGCUGAAGUCUGAAGUACUUUGCCUCAGGUUGAAACACAUCUUUGAGUCUCACAUGUCUGAUUUAGAUGAAAUUUUAGACUUCAGACUUUUGAAUUGAUCCUGGCCUGAGAUAAGACAUUGGGGCUAUUGGGAUGGAAUGAAUGUAUUUUGUAUGUGAGAAAGACAUAAAUUUGGGGGACUUGGGGUGGAAUGCCAUGGUUUGAAUGUUUGUGUCUCCUUAUGGCCUUAUCACUUCCCCAACGCAACUCUAUUAAGAGGUAUGGCUUUUGGGAAGUGAUAAGGUCAUGAGGGCUCCAGUCCCAUGAAUGGAUUCUUGCCCCCAUCAAAGGGCUGGAGAGAACUAGCUAGGAUCCCCUUUUUGCACUUCUGCAUUCUGCCAUGUGAGGGCACAGCAAGAAGGCCCUCACCAGACACCAAGUGCUGGCAUCUUGAUCUUGAACUUCCCAGCUUCUAGAACUGUGAGAAAUAGAUUUUGUUCUUUAUAAGUUAUCCAGUCUCAAGUAUUUUGUUAUAACUGCAGAAAUGAAUAAACACACACACAUACAUUGUAUAUAGUGUUCAAUUAAUAUAUUCACAGCUAUGUGCAACCGCCACCAUAGUCAAUUUUAGAACAAAAAGAGACCCUGCACCCUUUAGCUAUCAUACCCCCACUCCCUGCCAUCCCAUUGCUCCCCCUGCUUUCCCAACCCUAAGGAACUCUACUUUCUGUCUGCAUAGAUUUCCCUGUCCAGGACAUUUCAUGUGAAUAGAAUCGUCUGUGGUUUUUGUGAGUGUCUUCUUUCACUUAGCAUAAUGUUUUCAUGGUUAAUCUAUGUUGUAGCAUGCAUUAGUACUUCAUUCCUUUUUAUGGCUGAAUAAUAUUCCCUUGUAUGUGUAGUCCCAGCUGCUUGGGAGGUUGAGGCAGGAGAAUGGCAUGAACCCGGGAGGCGGAGCUUGCAGUGAGCUGAGAUCACGCCACUGCACUCCAGCCUGGGUGAUAGAGCGAGACUUCGUCUCAAAAUAAAUAAAUAAAUAAACAAACAAAUAAAUUCCCUUGUAUGUAUAUACUACUUUUUGUUUAUUCAACUGUUGAUGGACAUUUAUGUUUCUACCUUUUGGGUAUUGUGAAUAAUGCUUCUGUAAACAUUGGUGUAUAACUAUCUUUGAGUACUUGCUUUCCAUGUUUUUGUAUAUAUGUCUAGAUUAUAAUUGCUUCAUUAUAUGGUAAUUCUAUGCUUAGCUUUUUGAGGAACUGCCAAACUGUUUUCUAGAGCAGCUGCACCAUUUUACAUUCCCAAUAAUAAUGCACAAGGGUUUCAGUUUCUCCACAUUCUUGCCAACACUUGGCAUUUUUCGUUUCCUGUCCUCUCCUCUCCUCUCCUCUCCCCUCCCCUCCCCUCCCCUCCCCUGCCUUCCCCUCCCCUGCCUUCCCCUCCCCUCCCUUCCCCUUUCUCCCCUUCCCCUUCCCUUCCCCGUCCCCUUCCCCUUCCCCUUCCCUUCCCCUUCCCUUCCCAUUCCGCUUCCUCUUCCCUUGCCUUUCUUCCCCUUCCCCUUCCCCUUUCUUUCCUUAUAGCUGUCCUAAUAGGUGUUACAUCGUUUGGCUGUGUCCCAAAUCUCAUCUUGAAUUGUAGCUCCCAUAAUUUCCACAUGCUAUGGGAGGGACCUGGUGGGAGGUAAUUGAAUCACGGGGUUGGGUCUUUCCCAUGCUAUUCUAGUGAUAGUGAAUAAGUCUCAUGAGAUCUGAUGGUUUUAUAAAGGGGAGUUUCUCUGCACAAGUUCUCUUCUCUUGUCUGCCACCAUGUGAGACAUGCCUUUCACCUUCUGUCAUGAUUUUGAGGCCUCCUCAGCCACGUGGAAAUAUGAGUCCAUUAAACUUCUUUCUUUUGUAAAUUGCCCAGUUCUCUGAUAUGUCUUUAUCAGCAGCAUGAAAACGGACUAAUACAAGGCAUCAGAUGAUUGCUCAUUGUGGUUUUGAUUUGCUUUUUGUUACUCAGUUGUAGGAAUUUAUAUAUUCUAGAUAUUAAUACUCUUAUCAGUUAUGUGAUACGCAACUGUUUUGUCCUUUUCUGCAGGCUGUCUUUUCACUGUCUUCGUAGUGUCCUAUGACGCACAAAAAUUUUUAAUUUUUGAUGAAGUUCAUUUAUUUUAUUCUUUUGUUGCCUGUGCUGUUGGUGUCAUAUCUGAGUAGUCAUUGUCAAAUCCAAUGUCCAUAUAAAGAUUUUUGCAUAUGUUUUCUUCUAAGAGUUUAACAGAUAAUUUUAUUUCUUCCUUUCCAAUUUGGAUGGCUUUCAUUUCUUUUUCUUACUUAAUUGCUCUGGCUAGAGCUUCCAAUACUGUGUUAAGUAGAAGUGACAAAAGCAAGAAUUCUGUCUUGUUUCCACUCUUUGGGGAAAAGCUUUCACUAUUUCGCCAUUGAGUAUGAUGUUUGCUGUGGAAUUUAUAACAGACAUUAACAGAUAUUUAAUUCCCUUGCCUUGGUGGAAUGUUUCGGGAAUGAUUCUGUAUUCUUUGACUGUCCUGGGACUCUUGCAUCGAGAAUGUGGUCUAGAAGACCAGAACGAGGUGGCUGGGGAGUUGGGAGACACAAGUAACAUGAUUUUGUUUUAUGUUAUAGUGUGGCGUCAGUUCACCUUUCUUUCCAGACCUAGUGGCCAUUUUGUGGUCUUGAGGGUUACAGCAAAUGCCUUAGGUUUUGAGUGUCUUUCAGAGGCAAGGGGGGUUCUUAUACCAAGGUUCUCACAACUUUUUUCCCUUUUUGUCUUAAAAUGAUUGAGACCAUAGGGCCGUGGUGGUGUUGAAGGAGGUCGCCUGAAUAGAUCCACAUCCGCAUCACAAUUUCACUUCGCCUCUUGUACUUCAGUACCAGGUUUAGGGGACACAUGUGCCAUUCAAGUGAGGUUGGCUUUGUAAUGACUUUUCAGGGUGGAUUUUGGCUUCCUACAGGUAAGAACUUUCUACCUUUGUAAUAUCCUGACUCAUGAGUUGAAACAAUAGAUAUGAUGAAGGCCCAUGCCCCGUUUAGAAGAGUAAGUCUCAUGUUGCCAGGUCAGAAAUAGAUCCUCUUUCCUCUUGUUAAGCAUUGUGCUGAAUCCUGAGAGUGGUAAUCCUGCAGCAGGCAGAGAGAGGAGGACGUUGCCCUGAAGCUGUGGGGAGGCCUGGGGUUCAUUCCUACUGGGCUGCGGGUUCUGGUCUCUUCUACCAGUUUAAACAAAAUGGCACAGAUAGCCAAGAGCAGUAUCAGUUGAGAGUAGCACGAAUCUUGGGCGCUGAUGUGUGCUGUUUAGUUUUGGCUCCUGUUUUAACACAGGGAGAGGGCAGAUGGUGAAGCUCUGGCCACCUGUGAGUGUUGGCAACCCCAGGGGGGCAGUCCGUCCUGCUGGCUGUACUUUGAACUGGAAAUACUGGACAUAUGACAUUUUCCUUCUGACUCUCGCUGUUCGUGUGGCUUAUGCAGGAGGCAGGGGAGGAACAUUCUAAAUGACCUGGAGCUAUGCAUCUUGCCAGAAUCAACAAGCAGGACAAACCUUUGGGGAGAACAGUUGAGCCACUUUUCAAAGGCAGUGACCCUCUGGGACCCCCUACUUCAAACUGGCCCUGGAGGAGUAGACUGGUGGAGUGGACCGGAAUGGAAUGUCCUGCUGAUUGUGUGGAGCAGGCUGAGUAGCACAUGGUUUCUGGCCAGUGAUGUUCAUUUGUGUGGCCAGGUCUCAAAUUCAAUAUUGUUUUUAAGAAAAUCUUUCUGAAUGAAGAAGUCUCCAUGGACUCUUACUCCAUAAAAACUAAGAUUCUUUGCAGAGUUUCACUGGGCAGCAGUUCCAUGUCUAGGGGUGGAGGUUUGGCUUCUGUCAGACUGUUCCACAGGGCACAUUGAAGUCCUGGGUGCUGGGCAGGGCUGAGAUUCCCAGGGGAGCACCCCCAGGGCUGGGUCCUAGGGCGCCUUGACACUGUUAAAAAUUACUGAAGGCCCCAAAGAGCUGUGGUUAUGUGGCUGUAUAUAUUGAAAUUUACUAUUUUAGGAAUUGACAGGCAUUUAAAAAAUAUUUUUUCUCCAUGUAAAAAGAAUAUUCACCCAUUAUAUGUAAACAUAACAUCUUUUAUGGAAAAAAGCUGUAUUUUCAAAAACAAAAAAAAUGGGAAGAGUGUCAUUGUUUUGUACUUUUUAAAUCCCUUUAAUGUCUGCUUUAAGAGAAGGUAGUUGGAUCCCCCCAUCCCCCUGCCACCUGCAAUCAGUCUUAUGCUAUUUGGCCUCUAGAAAACUCCGCUGUGCAUUCGCGACGGAAUGCAAGGGACAAGGACACAUCGUAUCUUACUAUCUUGAAGAUAAUUUUGGCUUUACCACUCCUGGAGGUCUUGCCAUAGGGGUGAGGUCACUCAUACCAGGGUACCAUGUGAGAGGCUACCACAGGUGGAAGCACAGGUGUGGGGAUUUAGGCAGAGACCUUGGAGGCCAGGGGCUGCAACACCCCCUCACUGAAUUCAGAUAGAUGCUUGGGAACCACCAGUUCCUCUGCUUGUUCUCUUGUGUCUGUUGUUUGAAUCAGAAACUCAGCAGCUUAGGCCUCAGAGAGAUCUUGAGGAUACUUGGUCCGUAACUAUUAUGUGCCAAAUGAGGGAACUUACUUCUUCAGUCUUCUAGAAAAAUUUUAUCCCUUUUUGUGUUAAAACGUGGAUGCAGCCUGGAAGUGGUAAUGCUAGAUGCUGCAUACCACCUUGAUGGAACUAGAUGAAGUGAUUAGCUUCAGUCGCCUGAGUCUAGAGAGCCUGGGACCAGGCAGGGCAGCAGCAUUUGAGGGACUCUUGGGAAGCUUGGCACAGCUUGAGUGUGGGGGCUGUGAUGCACAAGCAUAGGCAGCUGUCUCUCUGUCUCUUCCCCCAGUGUUUGUUGAGCCAGUGUGAUGUGUCCUGUGUUGGCUGCCCAGGUAUAUACGACCGUUUCUAUCCUCAGGUCACCUUUACUGGGGGGAAGACUGAAGGUUUGUAAAAGAAACUGUGAUACCAACGUCAUUCGAUCAUCCACCCGAGAGUGCCUUGGAACAAAGGAGUGUUAAUCGACAGCAACGGGAGAAUAAGAAGGCUGGCUUUUUUUUUUUACCUGACAUGUAAAGGAGCUGAGGAGAGAAGGGUGUUGCAGAGAAAGCAGGGAUCUGCAUUCUCUUCCUCCCCACUGCUGUUGCAGGCUGACAGUCUUUGAGUACACACACAGAUGUGGCUGUGUUGUGCCCUGUCAGAGGCCCUGUGAGUCUCACCACCUCCUGAAGCACAAAGGUCCUUAGUGUGGUGCUCAGAGACCCCUGAACCAUGGGGUACAGGGUGCACAAAACUGGCCAUGAGCUGACUUUGUAGAAGGGCAGCCUUGGAGGGAGGGUGAGACAUUCAUGACCGUGGACCCAUUUUCCUCUGUCAGGAAGGAUGGGGGAAGUGAAGAGGACCUGAUCUAUAUUUGCCAAGAGAAGCUAAGCAGGUGGUUUUGGUGGAUAUGAAGGACAGGUUCUUUCUCGGGUCCCAGGACUCUCUUUCCUCCUGGGAAGCCCGACCUCCUGUGUGGCUCCAUGGCUCUGGUCAGAUUCCUGACUACUUAGCAUCACAACAGUGGAGGACAAUGGAAUUCUAAAAAGAUUCAGAGGAAACUUAGUAAUGUUAACAGGAGACAGUUUGAAAUUCGAUUGUUGUGACUCUUUCAAUGGCUCAAAUUGCGGAGAGGAGGAUGUGUAAUGAAAUGCUAAGAGUGGAUUUUGAUGGAGUGAAGGAAGUUUGAAUUAGCUUUGAUUAGAACACAGCCUCAUCAUGGGGACUCCAUUCUCAUGGGGAGUAGUGGAUGCUUUAAGAUGGAUUCCCCUGAGUUCAGAGGUGGGCAUCAGAAUGAUUUGCCUGCAUACCAGUCGUGUCUGUGGUCCCGGGUAGCUUUCUGUUCAUCAGCCCAGUGAAUGGGGCUCCACUUUUCUCCCUUUGGCUUUGCCUCUGUUCCAAGAAGUAAACGUCCUGAAAUAGAAAAGGAGGAGCUGUUCUUUGGCCAAUGAUUUGAGAAUAGCUAGAACUAAAGUUACCAACUGUGGAGGGCGGUUCCCUGUGGGCCUCAUCAACAGCUGAGGGCCCCCUUUCAGACACUUGUGAACAAGCUCCUCCAGAAUCCUUGCAUGCAGCUUUUGCAGAACUGAUAAAAGCAAUGGUCGGUCAUGCUUGCCACAAGCUGCUUCUGUUGAGAUCAUCAUUCUACGAUCUUGACCAAUGGGUGAAGUUUGGUUGCACUUUUGGCAUCUUGCAUUCACAGACCUACAGAAACCAGAUUAGGGAGCAUGUUGGAGGUGGCUCUGUAAGUGACAAUGCUAAGAUUGAGAACAUAGUGAUGACAUGGUAAGUGUGUACUGAGUGAAUUAAUGAAAGAAUACUGAAUUUCAGGACUAAGGGGAAACAUAGAGGUGAUUAUAAAGGAAGUGAAAACAGAACUCCCAGCUGACCACAAUGAACCUGGGGGUUUAUGAAGGCCUUAUUAGGGCAAUUGAAGUCUUAAUUUGGGGAUUGAAGGAGGUAGCAAUGGAGUCUUAAACUUUUCUACCCAAGUUACAAGAGCCAGGUAAAAAGAGAAUUAGUGCAGAAUCUGGUAUUUGAGCUUCCUGCAUCGAUUUUUCUAAAUUAUUUGCCAAAUUACAGGUUGUUUACUUUCUUUAGCUAAGGCACCACUCAGGGUUUGCCUUUAUCGUUGCACAGUUUGUCGCCAGGUCAUGGGAGCUGAGGCUGUGUCUAGGUGGCUGCAGGCCUGAGAGGUGUCAAUGAUGGAGUGGAGCUGGGGGUGUUGGGAGAGGUUUGAGCGGACCCAGCUGGGCAGCACCAUAGGGCUGCUGGGUAGGUAUUUUUGGGAAGCAGAAUGCUGAGCUCUCACUCAGAACCCCAGUGUAGGAGGCAGAUGAUUACCUGAGGCCCUCUGCACAGAGAAGGAACCAGCUUUGGAGAGCAUCAUGGGUUUCUGCUGCUUCCUCAACUGGUCUCCCCAGUUCCAGGAAGGCAGAACAGGUCAUUGAGAGGCACAGCUUGGGCUUCUCGAUUGCAACACAGGAGCAAAGUGGUAGAUGGGUCAUGUCUGUGAACGAGGUGUGAGCAGCCCAGUGUAGGACACAGUCAGGGUCCCCAACAUGGCGGGCCUAGUGGCUCACUGCUGGGUCUGAUUUAAGAAAGAUACCUGGAUAGGACGAUGUAAGAACUGUCUUUGGGUCCCCAAGGAUGGGUUGGGAGCUGAAAUGUACCCCCUGCUGGCCAGGAGCCGCAGGGACUCUUGUAGGUAUGGAGGGUAUGGCAUGGGGGCUGCCAUACUGUGACUCAAGAGUGCGAUGGGUGGAUGUGGGCCUCAAAGUGGGCCAGCUCUGCCCAGACCAGAGCAUUCUGCUUCCUGUGGAGCAUCCCUGAAGUCCUUGUGACCGUGUGGCCAGAGAGCAUGGUCUUGGGGCAGGCAGAUGACAAGAGGCCGUACCAGGAUGGAAGUCGUCUGCAUUUGGAGGCAGGAAACAACACAGGACUCCCUGCAGUUGUUAAGUGUACUCUUAAGGUGUCCCAUGCUUGCCUGCACCUGCCUGCCCUAUACCUUCAGGAUCCAGGUGUCCUUUUGGAACUGGAGGAUCAGGAGCCAGAGGGGCCGGCAGUCUGGUACUCCUGCCUUGGGCAUCUGUGCGGGCAUUCUGGUAUUCCUGCCUUGGACUUCCCGGCAGCCAGGCAGUGGGUACCUGGGAGGAUGUUGCACCAGUCUGUGCAGGAGACCAAGAGAACUAAAUACUGGAGAUCAUGCACACUCAUUAAAAAAGAAUACUGCAGAAAAGUUCGAUUACAUUGCUAGAUAAAGUCAUUUUUAAUGUGUCCAUACCCUGUGUCAGUUUUCAAUCUUGUGCUACUGUAUGAUAGUGAUGCAUUUCAGAGCCAUUAAUCAUUGUUUACCAACCAUUCCUGUUUGUAGGAACCCUCUGUUUCCAUUGUCUUUGCAAAAUUCUUGAUUUUCUGAGUUGAGGAUUGGUUUUCCUUAUUCAUGUUUAUAUAGACAUUACCCUGAAAACCUAGAACACACAGUAGUUACUUACUGAAUGUACUAAUGAUAUAGAGAAUGAAAAGAUAUCAUCAUCUUUAGAAUAGAAUGCCAGGCCCUAGUGGGCUCUGGUGUGUGUGCUGGUGAUGGGCUAAUGUUGAUAACUGGCUGUUUGGGGGUGGUGAUAAAGCGUCCAAAGCACAUUGACUGUUUCCCUACAGCUUUCUUCAUUGAGGAGAGGAGAGAUCUUUAUCAACUGUGCACGCCUCUCCACUCCAAACUAUUUACUCCUCGCACAGUUUUAACGAUUACAAUUACAUUAUGUUUCCUCCACAAGCAAGAAUGUCUUUCCUCUUUACUUUUGAGGUGUAUCCUUUUUUCUUUAACCCGCCCCUUUUUUUUAAAACUCCUUUAACUUUUUUUAAAACUCCUUUAAGGGAAGAAGAAAAGGAAAAGAAAGGAAGAAAAAGAAAAGAAAAUAGAAGGGCAAAGUCUUUCAGUAUUUCCAGAAGCUGCCUGUAUAGAAAAGGGCCUGUGCAGUUAAUAUUCAUGUGACUUGGCCUCAAGCACUUAAUAGCCUCAUUGUGUUUAGGUAUAGAGCAGUGAUUUCUCUGGAAUUCCUAGAAAGGGAGGGGGAGCCCUCCACAAGGGCAGAGGGGGAUCACAAGGGACCCUGAGUAUAGGUUUUUGUGUGAGGAGAAGCAUAUAGGACCCUUGGCCUGAAACUGGAUGAAAACAUUCUUUCUUAGAUAAAUUUUAAAGUUGCAUGAGUAAUUUGUGAUCUUUAUUUUAAAUAGUCGAACCCAGAAGUCUGUAGAGAGUGAAAUUCUCACUUCACUUCUCAUGGCCCUCCUUUGAGGUUGGUGUUCAGGGUUCUUUUGGCUCCUUUUGCUCUGCGGAAUUAACUAAUUACUUUUUAAUUGAUGCAUAAUAGAUAAACAUAGUUUCAAGGUACAUGAGAUAAUUUAAUGCAUGCAUGUAAUUUGUAAAGGUCAAAUCAGUGUACUUAAUAUACCCACCACCUUAAAUAUUUGUCUUAACUUUAGAAACAUUCAAAUUCUUCUCUUCUUGCUAUUUUGAAGUGUACAAUAGAUUAUUGUAGACGGUAGUCACCUUAUUGAUUUAUUUAAUUAAGUGUACUUAUUUCAAGAAUGAGCAGAAAUAAGGCCUAGUAUUAUAUAAAUCAAUAAGGUGACCAUAUAUUUGUACUCAUUAAUCAACUUUUUUUUAAUCCUCCAUACCCCCCUACUCUUCCCUGUCUCUGGUAACCACCAAUCUACUCUCUGUCUUCAUGAGAUCCACUUCAUAGCUUGCACAUGAGUGAGAACAUGUCAUAUGUCUUUCUAUGCCUGUCUUCCAGGUUAAUGCAUGCUGUUGCAAAUGAUAGAAUUUCACUCCUUUUUUAUGGUUGAAUAGCACUCCACUGUGUGUAUGUACCACCUUUUUUAAAUGAGUUCAUUGUUGUUGGACACUUAGAUCGAUUCCAUAUCUUGGCUAUUGUGAAUAAUGCUGCAGUAAACACGGGUGUGCAGAUAUCUUUUUGAUACAGAUCCUUUCUUUUGGGUAUAUACCCAGCAGUGAAAUUGCUGGAUCAUAUGAUAGUUCUAUUUUUAGUUUUCUGAGGAACCUCCAUAUUGUUCUCCAUGGGGGCUGCACUAAUUUACAUUCCCACCGGCAGAGUAUAGGGGGUCCCCUUUGGUACAUUCUCCCCAGUAUCCAUUAUUCCCUUUUUGAUAAUAGUCAUUUUAACUGGGGUGAGAUGAUAUCUUAUUGUGGUUUUGAUUUGUAUUUCCCUGAUAAAUAUUGGUGUUGAGCAUUUUUUGGAUACACCUGUUGGCUCUUUGUAUGUCUUCUUUUAGAGAUGUCUGUUCACAUGUUUUGCCCAUUUUUAAAUUGAGUUACUUGUUUUUUUGCUAUGGAAUUGUUUGAACUCCUUAUACAUUCUGGUUAUUAAUCUCUUGUCAGAUGAGUAGUUUGCAAAUAGUUUCUCUCAUUUUCUCUGUUUGGAAUUCCUGGGUGCAGACACCCACAGAUAUACUGCUUUCCCCUUUUUACGGCAGUGUUGCUUAUUCCUGGUGCUUAGCUCUUUGCCUCCUUUAUUAAACACUUGCCUUCUGUCAGUGCUGUGUGAAGCACUCUGUGGGAAUUGCAUCAUUUCAUCCUUGCAUGAAGUUGGGACGGUUUUGUUCUCAGUUUACAGUUGAGGAAAUUGAGGCAGAGAGUGGCUGAGCGCUUGUGCAGGCUGCCCCCACCCCAGCUGGUGGAGGCUGGGUUCUGAGCCACUUUCACAGCUGCCUCCCACAGACCAGAGCUCAUGUCCCUGUGGCUCCUUUAGAGCUUUUGCGUGCCUUCCAGUGCUGCUUUCCAUGCUGGAGGAGUACUGUGCUCUACUAUAUUUAAGUCGGCUCCUGUCCAGGCAUUUUUUUCCAUAAGUUCAGCAAAGAUUUGAGCCACUUGGCCCUGUGCUAAGAGAUGGGAUACAGCAGUAGUCAGGACAGAUAGAGUUCUCGGCCUCAGAGCUACCUCUUCUUGGGAAAGGGACACAAAAAAAGUUGGCAGGAAGAAGAACAGCACUAGCAAGCCUGAUGUGUUCUGCAGAAGAGGCAGCCAAGGGCUGAGCUAUAGACCCAUGUGGAGAGGGUCUGGAGUGGGUCAGGCGGCCUGAUCCCUCAGGGUGGACAGGGACAGGACAGGGUGGAUGGGGAGCCUUGGUUCUCUGAGGAGGCUACCAGCAGGGGAAGGUGGAAGGCAGCUGGGGCCACAGGUGUUUGAAAAAAUUCCAAAUACAAGGCAGAGAGCAUGCAAAGGCCAUGAGGGAGGAUAGAGUCUGAGAACCUGGAGGAGGCCAGGCUGGUGAGUGAGGUGACUCCAGCAUGGGACAGCAGUGUCUGGGCAGCCUGGAGAGGAGGCAGGGGCCACACGCGUCAGGCCUGGCAGCUGUCGCUGAGAAUUUGGGUGCAUUUGAAGUACAGAGGGCAAUGGUGUCACCUCAUGGGCUCCCCAGAGCUAGGGCUGGUUAAGUGGGAAGCAGUGAGGAUGCUUAGAGACAGGGCAGCUGAGUCCCAGUUCAGAUGAGGGGCAGAGGCCUGGAGUUGGCAGCAGAGAUGGAAGGGAGUGGAUGACUCUCAGAUGCUUCCGCAGCCAAUGAGCUGGGCUAGCGGAUUACAUGGAUGGAAGGCAGAAGAGAAAGUUAGGAAUGGAGAGCUCUUGUUUCUGCCUUGUGCAGUUUGGUGGGUGCCAUGAACUGGGGGAGAGGAGGGAUUUGGGCAGCCACAUUUAGGUUGCUUCCAGUUUUUCUGUCUUAAAGUGUGUAGUAAACAUUCCGUGUGUGUGUAUGCACGCGUGUGUAUGCAUGUGAGUCUUUCUGUAGGAUAAGCUAUUCCAAGAAGGAUGCCUGUGCCUAAGACUAAAGUCUGAAAGCUGCUGCCCCCACUCCAGCGGGCCUCCCCAUGCCUGUACAGUGUGAUCCCACCUCCGGUUUAGGGGAGCCCUGUUGCUGUUCAGCCAUCCUCAACUCUGGGUAGUCCCAGUCCUUUUAAUUUUCAGCUAUCAAUUAUAGCUCAUGUGUUUGUAUAUGUCUCCCUGGCUCCUAGUGAAGUUUAGCAUGUUUCACAUGUCUGUUUUGCAAAUUGUUUGCUUCUAUCCUCUCCCCAUUUUUAUGUUGGGCUGCUUACAUCCUAUCUCUUAUUUCAGUAAAGAAGAGAUUAAAUUCAGAUUGUUGGCUGUGUGGUAAUGGAAAUAUUUUGUCCCAAGGCUUUUUUUUUUUUUUGGAGACGGAGUCUUGCUCUGUCGCCCAGAGUGGAGUGCAGUGGCACGAUCUCGGCUCGCUGCAAGCUCCGCCUCCCAGGUUCAUGCCAUUCUCCUGCCUCAGCCUCCUGAGUAGCUGGGACUACAGGCGUCCACCACCAUGCUCAGCUAAUUUUUUUGUAUUUUUAGUAGAGAUGGGGUUUCACCGUGUUAGCCAGGAUCGUCUCCAUCUCCUGACCUCAUGAUCCACCUGCCUCAGCCUCCCAAAGUACAGGGAUUACAGGCGUGAGCCACUGCGCCCCGCCGGCUUUUUGCCUGUCUUUUGAUUUGUCUAUAGGGUCUUUUGCUGAACAGAAGUUAGUUUUUUCUUCAUGGCUUCUAGGUUGAGAAUCUUGCUUAUGAAGAUCUUCCUCACUCAGAUUUUAUAACAUUUUUCUUCUGUACUAUCUCUUAGUAGUUUAGUAGUUCUUGUAAUGUUUAAGGCACAUAUGGAAGGUGAGGAUAUGACCGUGGGAUCUUACUGAGCAUAAGUUGCCAGCUAUCCAUGAUCUUAUUUUUAAUUUAUGUGUCAUCAUUCACCUCUGGCUGCAUUCUCUUACUUUUAUUCUGUAAAUGGACAUGUCUGUUCCUGUAUCUGUAAAUCAGCAAGCUGAGUUCCUUGAAGACAGGGCCUUCCUUGGGAUGAUAUUGCUUUAACUUACUGAAGUGGAGGUGGAGUGUCCGUCAGCAAUGUGAGGGCUUCCCUUUAAAGGAGGUGGUGCAUUUCUAACCCUUCUGAUCUUCUUUUGGCUUCCUCAAAAAUUUUUUAUUUUCUUCAAAGGAUCUCGUAUGUAUUCUUAAGUGUGUUGUUUUGGUUGCUUCUGCUAAUUAAAUCAUUUUCACCAUUAGACUUCCUAGGUGUCUUGGAGCUGCUGUGCAGAAGGGCUGGGGAGGGUUUGUAGUUUGCUCUGGGAUCGCAAUCUUACUAAACGUUCAGAUCGGUUCUAAUUAUUUUUCAGUGCAUGGUCUUACAUUUCAUCUGUAAAUAGUGACGGUGUAUUAGUCUGUUCUUGCACUACUACAAAGGAAUAGUUGAGACUGGGUAAUUCAUAAAGAAAAGAGGUUUAAUUCACUCUUGAUUCCGCAGGCUGGACAGGAAGCACGGCAGCAUCUACUCGGCUUCUGAGGCGUCCUCAGGAAACCUACAAUCAAGGUGGAAGGCGACAGGGGAAGCAGACAUGUUUUAUGUGGCUGGAGGAAGAGGAAGAGAAGUGGGGGGAGGUGCCACACACUUAAACAACCAGGUCUCUUGAGAACUCCAUCACAACAGCACCACGAGGAUGGUGCUAAACCAUUCAUGAAGGAUCCACCACCACAGUCCAGUCACCUUCCACCAGGCUCCACCUCCAACACUGGGGGUUACAAUUUGAAAUGAGAUUUGCUUUGGCGCUGACCACAAUGCUGAGCAGGAAGCAGCAGCUGCAGGCCCAGUGACUGGUAGCUCAGUGACCAGCAGCCCAGUGACCGGCAGCCAGGUCCUCACCUGGGUCCUCUCAGUGAAGCCAGGGUGGCCGCCCCAGCAGACAGUGCUACAGAGCCAACUCCUGACAGAGGAUGAUGUGGACCUGGAAGCCCUGGUGAACGAUAUGAAUGCAUCCCUGGAGAGCCUGUACUCGGCCUGCAGCAUGCAGUCAGACACGGUGCCCCUCCUGCAGAAUGGCCAGCAUGCCCGCAGCCAGCCUCGGGCUUCAGGCCCUCCUCGGUCCAUCCAGCCACAGGUGUCCCCGAGGCAGAGGGUGCAGCGCUCCCAGCCUGUGCACAUCCUCGCUGUCAGGCGCCUUCAGGAGGAAGACCAGCAGUUUAGAACCUCAUCUCUGCCGGCCAUCCCCAAUCCUUUUCCUGAACUCUGUGGCCCUGGGAGCCCCCCUGUGCUCACGCCGGGUUCUUUACCUCCGAGCCAGGCCGCCGCAAAGCAGGAUGUUAAAGUCUUUAGUGAAGAUGGGACAAGCAAAGUGGUGGAGAUUCUAGCAGACAUGACAGCCAGAGACCUGUGCCAAUUGCUGGUUUACAAAAGUCACUGUGUGGAUGACAACAGCUGGACACUAGUGGAGCACCACCCGCACCUAGGAUUAGAGAGGUGCUUGGAAGACCAUGAGCUGGUGGUCCAGGUGGAGAGUACCAUGGCCAGUGAGAGUAAAUUUCUAUUCAGGAAGAAUUACGCAAAAUACGAGUUCUUUAAAAAUCCCAUGAAUUUCUUCCCAGAACAGAUGGUUACUUGGUGCCAGCAGUCAAAUGGCAGUCAAACCCAGCUUUUGCAGAAUUUUCUGAACUCCAGUAGUUGUCCUGAAAUUCAAGGGUUUUUGCAUGUGAAAGAGCUGGGAAAGAAAUCAUGGAAAAAGCUGUAUGUGUGUUUGCGGAGAUCUGGCCUUUAUUGCUCCACCAAGGGAACUUCAAAGGAACCCAGACACCUGCAGCUGCUGGCCGACCUGGAGGACAGCAACAUCUUCUCCCUGAUCGCUGGCAGGAAGCAGUACAACGCCCCUACAGACCACGGGCUCUGCAUAAAGCCAAACAAAGUCAGGAAUGAAACUAAAGAGCUGAGGUUGCUCUGUGCAGAGGACGAGCAAACCAGGACGUGCUGGAUGACAGCGUUCAGACUCCUCAAGUAUGGAAUGCUCCUUUACCAGAAUUACCGAAUCCCUCAGCAGAGGAAGGCCUUGCUGUCCCCGUUCUCGACGCCAGUGCGCAGUGUCUCCGAGAACUCCCUCGUGGCAAUGGAUUUUUCUGGGCAAACAGGACGCGUGAUAGAGAAUCCGGCAGAGGCCCAGAGCGCAGCCCUGGAGGAGGGCCACGCCUGGAGGAAGCGAAGCACACGGAUGAACAUCCUAGGUAGCCAAAGUCCCCUCCACCCUUCUACCCUAAGUACAGUGAUUCACAGGACACAGCACUGGUUUCACGGGAGGAUCUCCAGGGAGGAAUCCCACAGGAUCAUUAAACAGCAAGGGCUCGUGGAUGGGCUUUUUCUCCUCCGUGACAGCCAGAGUAAUCCAAAGGCAUUUGUACUCACACUGUGUCAUCACCAGAAAAUUAAAAAUUUCCAGAUCUUACCUUGCGAGGACGACGGGCAGACGUUCUUCAGCCUAGAUGACGGGAACACCAAAUUCUCUGACCUGAUCCAGCUGGUUGACUUUUACCAGCUGAACAAAGGAGUCCUGCCUUGCAAACUCAAGCACCACUGCAUCCGAGUGGCCUUAUGACCGCAGAUGUCCUCUCGGCUGAAGACUGGAGGAAGUGAACACUGGAGUGAAGAAGCGGUCUGUGCGUUGGUGAAGAACACACAUCGAUUCUGCACCUGGGGACCCAGAGCGAGAUGGGUUUGUUCGGUGCCAGCCGACCAAGAUUGACUAGUUUGUUGGACUUAAACGACGAUUUGCUGCUGUGAACCCAGCAGGGUCGCCUCCCUCUGCAUCGGCCAAAUUGGGGAGGGCAUGGAAGAUCCAGCGGAAAGUUGAAAAUAAACUGGAAUGAUCAUCUUGGCUUGGGCCGCUUAGGAACAAGAACCGGAGAGAAGUGAUUGGAAAUGAACUCUUGCCCUGGAAUAAUCUUGACAAUUAAAACUGAUAUGUUUACUUUUUUUGUAUUGAUCACUUUUUUGCACUCCUUCUUUGUUUUCAAUAUUGUAUUCAGCCUAUUGUAGGAGGGGGAUGUGGCGUUUCAACUCAUAUAAUACAGAAAGAGUUUUGAAUGGGCAGAUUUCAAACUGAAUAUGGGUCCCCAAAUGUUCCCAGAGGGUCCUCCACACCCUCUGCCGACUACCACGGUGUGGAUUCAGCUCCCAAAUGACAAACCCAGCCCUUCCCAGUAUACUUGAAAAGCUUUCUUGUUAAAAUAAAAGGUGUCACUGUGGUAGGCAUUUGGCAUAUUUUGUGGACUCAGUCAAGCAACCACAGUCUGUUAAUCAUUUCUCUAUGCUCAGAUGUCAGAUCCUCUUGUUAUUAGUGUGUCUUGUUCUGCACAGUGCAGGAGACUUUAUUCCUUUGGAAAAUUCACUGUUCCACAAACAGCAGGCUGAAUGGCCUCGCCUCUAGAUUGACGUGGGCCAGCCUCCUUGAGACACACCUGGCACCCGUCAUCGGCCAGCGGUGGAUGCUGCAUAAUCCACCUGGGUACUUCAGCCUUGCGUUUCCACAGCCUUCAGCCUGUUCUAGAACGAUCACUGCCUUACCCCUGCUGCUGCAGUGGUGUGAGUCGUUUCACGGCUGAUGUCCCUCGGGGGAUUAAAGGAUCUAAAGAGAAAAUGGCACCUGGUUGUCUUCGUGCUGUGUCUCAUGGGUUUCCAUAGUGAUAAAGACAAGGAAACGCUGCAGGGGCCACAGGCACAGGCUGAUAUUUAAAGAUCUUUGCUUGCAGCCCUCCGUCCUGCUGAAAACCCCCAUAAGCCAGUGAACACAGAGCAGCUAGAGGCUCCUCCUCUGCUGGCUUAGGGUCAGAAGUACCUCACAGUGGUUGUGGACAUGGAAGAGUUUUGUCAACACAACACUUUGUCCCCGCUCCGGGAGAUGAGUCAGAUGGUGGCUUGAGUUGUCACUUGGUCCCCUCCGCCCCUCGGGUGGCCCCCUUUGCCACGUCCCCUUAGCUUAGUGAUCAGGUGUGAGAGUGGCCAUUUCCUUACCUUUGAUCCCUGUAAAGCAGAAAGGACUCCUUUGACAGGCGACAAACUACUGUGGUGAGCAGAAUGAUUUCCUUUUUCAAGACAACACCUGCCUGGCUUCUAUUAAUGUGUGCUGGCCAUGAUAUUGCCCCAAAUCCGCCCCACUGAAGUGUUCCCUAAGGAACAGCAUUUCUCUGCUCCUCAGUCAACCCCCGUAGCCUAGAGCAGUGUCACAAGCUUCAGUAAGGCCAGUCAGCUGGAAGUCAGUCUACCGUAUAGUAACACUGUAUGUCAGUCUACAGACCACACUCUAGUUGUUUUCCAUGAAAGGUAUACAAAUGAAGAAUUUUCUAGCAAAACAUGUUUUUAACCAUCAGUGCUCAAUUGCAUUUUCUUCCUUUCGCAGCCAGUCAGUCUUUCAAACUAUUGACAGUAAGAUAAUUCUCACGUUCACACCUGGUGGCAGGCUUCACUGUAGGGACGGACAUUGCAGUUACACCACGAUUCCUUCCUCUUCACUGGCUCGAGGUAAACCCUUUUCAAGGAAAAACAACUCUAGGAUUUCUUUUUUCUGUGUACGUAGACCAGUCCCAUCAGUGUAUAAUCUCUCUCUCACACGCCUCUCUCCAAUAGACAGCUUGUAUUUGCAGUAUUUCAUAUUUAUAAAUAUGCGUUUAUUUAAAAGGAGAACAAAAGCUUGACUCUGAUUCACAGUUUUGUAUGUAGCUGGUUUGACGUAGUCUUUUGUAUUUUCCCUGCCGAAGUGAAUUGUUGGAGAAUGUAAACCGCCUCCACGUGGCGGCAGACUUCCUAAGGCCCCAGCUCGCUGGCCUCGCGCUGGGCGGCUGGGAAUUCCACCUGAGAACAAGUCCCGCAAACCGGGGACGGAAGGACAUUUGACUUUUAUUUUUGUAUUUAAUUGACAUGAAUGUAAAGGGGACAGCUCAGGGUUGUUUUGGAGCCUGUUGACUUUGUAUCUCUGCCUGUGAUUUUCUUUUCUAAAUGAAACUCCAUGUAGCAACCAGGACGAAGUUGAGAAGGAAAACGCCAAAUGCUUUGGUUAUUAGAGUUUAAUAGGUAAGCUCUGUUACACUAGGUGUUAGAGUUCCAGAAUGUUCUUUUGUUUGCUAAACCUUGAAGAAACAUGUGCCUCAGCCUAGAUGUUUUGUCUUCUCUUUUCUGCACUUAAUACCUGACAGUAUGACCGAUCUCUGCGCCUUUCUGGGGGCGGGCAAGCUGGCGGUAGAUUUGUGAUGUCACAGUGCAAACUGCAGUGACUGUAAAUUGGCCUGGCGUGUAUAAACGUUUUCAGGGAAUGCAGAAGGUAUUAAUGAAGAGACAAAACCUUUAUUCCAUGUGCUUUGCUUCAUUCUGUACAUAGCUCUUUGGCUCGUGAACCUAAUUGUAAACUUUCAGGUAUUUUUGUACAAAUAAGGGACUGAUGUUCUGUUUCUUGUAAUUAGAAAUAAACAUUAAUACAGUGUUCUUCA